AGUCCCCGUUACCCUCUGCUUUUUCUGCUCCUCAGAGUCAACAGCUGUUGCAGCAUGAGCGAUACGCUUGGUUCUCCUAACUAGCACCUUCCCCUCUCCCCUGACUCAGCUGGUAGCCCCUCCUCCCCGCACCUGCCCAAAGGUCACUGGACAGGCAUUUGUCUGGCCUUCCCUUUUACUGCUGGCUGGGAAGGAGGAGCAUCAGACCACAGAUCCUGGAAGGCACUUCUCUCCCUGACUGCUGCUCACACUGCCGUGAGAACCUGCUUAUAUCCAGGACCAAGGAGGCAAUGCCAGGAAGCUGGUGAAGGGUUUCCUCUCCUCCACCAUGGUUGACAGCACUGAGUAUGAAGUGGCCUCCCAGCCUGAGGUGGAAACCUCCCCUUUGGGUGAUGGGGCCAGCCCAGGGCCGGAGCAGGUGAAGCUGAAGAAGGAGAUCUCACUGCUUAACGGCGUGUGCCUGAUUGUGGGGAACAUGAUCGGCUCGGGCAUCUUUGUUUCCCCCAAGGGUGUGCUCAUAUACAGUGCCUCCUUUGGUCUCUCUCUGGUCAUCUGGGCUGUCGGGGGCCUCUUCUCCGUCUUUGGGGCCCUUUGUUAUGCGGAACUGGGCACCACCAUUAAGAAAUCUGGGGCCAGCUAUGCCUAUAUCCUGGAGGCCUUUGGAGGAUUCCUUGCUUUCAUCAGACUCUGGACCUCCCUGCUCAUCAUUGAGCCCACCAGCCAGGCCAUCAUUGCCAUCACCUUUGCCAACUACAUGGUACAGCCUCUCUUCCCGAGCUGCUUCGCCCCUUAUGCUGCCAGCCGCCUGCUGGCUGCUGCCUGCAUUUGUCUCUUAACCUUCAUUAACUGUGCCUAUGUCAAAUGGGGAACCCUGGUACAAGAUAUUUUCACCUAUGCUAAAGUAUUGGCACUGAUCGCGGUCAUCGUUGCAGGCAUUGUUAGACUUGGCCAGGGAGCCUCUACUCAUUUUGAGAAUUCCUUUGAGGGUUCAUCAUUUGCAGUGGGUGACAUUGCCCUGGCACUGUACUCAGCUCUGUUCUCCUACUCAGGCUGGGACACCCUCAACUAUGUCACUGAAGAGAUCAAGAAUCCUGAGAGGAACCUGCCCCUCUCCAUUGGCAUCUCCAUGCCCAUUGUCACCAUCAUCUAUAUCUUGACCAAUGUGGCCUAUUAUACUGUGCUAGACAUGAGAGACAUCUUGGCCAGUGAUGCUGUUGCUGUGACUUUUGCAGAUCAGAUAUUUGGAAUAUUUAACUGGAUAAUUCCACUGUCAGUUGCAUUAUCCUGUUUUGGUGGCCUCAAUGCCUCCAUUGUGGCUGCUUCUAGGCUUUUCUUUGUGGGCUCAAGAGAAGGCCAUCUCCCUGAUGCCAUCUGCAUGAUCCAUGUUGAGCGGUUCACACCAGUGCCUUCUCUGCUCUUCAAUGGUAUCAUGGCAUUGAUCUACUUGUGCGUGGAAGACAUCUUCCAGCUCAUUAACUACUACAGCUUCAGCUACUGGUUCUUUGUGGGGCUUUCUAUUGUGGGUCAGCUUUAUCUGCGCUGGAAGGAGCCUGAUCGACCUCGUCCCCUCAAGCUCAGCGUUUUCUUCCCGAUUGUCUUCUGCCUCUGCACCAUCUUCCUGGUGGCUGUUCCACUUUACAGUGAUACUAUCAACUCCCUCAUCGGCAUUGCCAUUGCCCUCUCAGGCCUGCCCUUUUACUUCCUCAUCAUCAGAGUGCCAGAACAUAAGCGACCGCUUUACCUCCGAAGGAUCGUGGGGUCUGCCACAAGGUACCUCCAGGUCCUGUGUAUGUCAGUUGCUGCAGAAAUGGAUUUGGAAGAUGGAGGAGAGAUGCCCAAGCAACGGGAUCCCAAAUCUAACUAAACACCAUCUGGAAUCCUGAUGUGGAAAGCAGGGGUUUCUGGUCUACUGGCUAGAGCUAAGGAAGUUGAAAAGGAAAGCUCACUUCUUUGGAGGCACCUGUCCAGAAGCCUGGCCUAGGCAGCUUCAACCUUUGAACUUACUUUUUGAAAUGAAAAGUAAUUUAUUUGUUUUGCUACAUACUGUUCCAGACUUUUAAAGGGGACAAUGAAGGUGACUGUGGGGAGGAGCAUGUCAGGUUUGGGCUUGGUUGUUUUAGAAGCACCUGGGUGUGCCUACCUACUCCUCUUUUCUUUUAAAAGGGCCCACAAUGCUCCAAUUUCCUGUCUCCUUUAGAGAGACAUGAAACUAUCACAGGUGCUGGAUGACAAUAAAAGUUUAUGUUCCUAAA